GCUCACCGUAACCUUGAACUCCUGGGCUCCUCUGCCUCAGCCUCCCAAUUAGCCACCACACCCAGCUACCUUUUGUACAUUUUUUUGGUAGAGACGGUGUCUCACUAUGUUGCCCAGUCUGGUCUCAAACUCCUCAGCUCAAAUGAUCUGCCCACCUUGACCUCCAGAGAUACUGGGAUUACAGGCGUGGGCCACUGCACCAGACCCAGGUUUAUUCUUACACCAAUACAACACUGUCUUAAUUACUAUAGCUUUGUAGUGAGCUUUUGAAAAUAGGAAAUGUGAAUCCUCCAACUUUUUUUUUUUGGAGACGGAGUCUCGCUCUGUUGCUCAGACUGGAGUGCAGUGGCACUAUCUCAGCUCACUGCAAACUCCAUCUUCCAGGUUCAAGUGAUUCUCCUGCCUCAGCCUACCAAGUAUCUGGGACUACAGGCAGGUGCCACCAUGCACAGAUUCCUUGGACAUCCCUGAGAGGUCAAUCAUGAAGGUCAACUUGGUUUUCUCCCCCUCAUUUGGGUUCAGAAUUUAAAGUCCACACACACAGGCAGUAAGAUGAUUAUAGAUAAGGACAUCAUCACUCGGUUUCGGAUGUUAAAUUGUCUAGGUGGGUUAGGGGUGAUUUGAGAUCACACAACCUUGUGCCACAAAGAGGAAUUCCCAGGCCAGAGGGAGACAUUUUAUUGCCAUGUUAUGAUCUUAUCAUUGAGUUGAAAGGCAAUCUUGUUUCAUUUUGGAUUCUUUCUUAUGUUUAUGUCUUAUAAGGGCACUUUGAAUUUCCAAGCAAAUAAUAAUUUUGAAUUAGCUUUUAAUCAUUGACUUCUAGCACAGUUAUAUGAUCAGAAACGUGCUGUGUGAUUUGAUUGCUCUCAAAUAUAUUGAGAUUUGCUGGAACAAAAUAAGUCAGGUUAAUUUUUGUAAAUGUACCAUGCUUGCUUAAAAUGAAUGUAUCUACAUUUGUUCCUGAGAUACGGGUUGAUGGACGGAUGGCUACAUGGAUGUGAUGGAGAUGGUUUACUAUCGGGACCUUCCGCAUCCUGCUGAUGUUUUGUUGCUUAGGAUAUGAAUGGCUGAGCGGAGGCUGUAAAACCUGGCACUCUGCUUGGGUAUGAGGUUCUUCCUGCCAUCCUGCCAUCAUUUGUUUUUUAUGUUUUGUCGCCAAAAGUGACCUUGAGGAACCCUGGGAGCUCAGGAAGGAAGGAGCGCCCAGAAGCAGGGACAGGGAGCUGGUUGGGGAGGACCAGAAAUCAGGUUUGUGAAGGUUCCAGAGAGGACCUGUCCUUGCGAGGAGUGUGGGAGACUGAGAUGGGGGAGGGGUCAUUGGAAUGAUGCGGGCGCUACUUGGCAUUGUCCAUUGUGAGGCACCACCGGGGUCAUCAGGGAUUGGUGGAGAGGGAGUAUAAAGCCCCAGGUUUGCUAAGGGAGGGCCCAGACCGAAGAAGGUUUGGCGGAUAGCAGAACCUUUUUGUCUCCCUCUAAUUGCUCCUAAGCCUCACGCUCCCUUGCCCCGCGUGUCCUGUUGCUUCCCUGAUCUUCUCCGUGACCUGUAGCUAAACCUUCCACCAGCGCUUGAGAACUUAAUUUGAACCGGAUCCUUUCCCAGACCCCUUUCUUCUUCUCCUCCUCCACCUCCUCCAGGUGCCCAACAGCCCCCUUCUCCUCCUUUCCCUUCCCUUACUUCCCCCCUUCCCCUCCCCUUCCCCUCCCCCUCCCCUCCCCUUCCCCUCCCCUUCCCCUUCCCCUCCCCCUCCCCUUCCCCUCCCCCUCCCCUUCCCCUCCCCCUCCCCUCCCCCGCCCCAACUCAGAUCCGGCCCCGGUCCCCGUCCCCUUCCCUCCCCCCUGCCCUAAGCCACCUCCACCUCUGUCCUGGCCGCCUCAGGGCACCCUGAAAGGAUCAGGACAUGCGGCUGCGCUUUUGGCUCCUCAUUUGGCUCCUGCUGGGAUUUAUCAGCCAUCAGCCCACCCCUGUUAUCAAUAGUCUGGCUGUCUAUCGUCAUCGUGAGACUGACUUUGGUGUAGGAGUUCGAGACCACCCUGGCCAACAUGGCAAAACCCCAUCUCCACAAAAAUUGGAUAAUUUGAUAAUUAUCAUUAUUGGGUUUCUGAGACGUUACACAUUUAACGUUCUCUUCUGCACAAGUUGCCUUUGUGUGUCUUUCCUGAAGACUAUCUUCUGGUCUCGAAAUGGACAUGAUGGAUCCAUGGAUGUACAGCAGAGAGCCUGGAGGUCCAACCGCAGUAGACAGAAAGGGCUGAGGUCCAUUUGUAUGCACACAAAGAAAAGAGUUUCUUCCUUUCGAGGAAAUAAAAUUGGCCUGAAAGACGUCAUUACUCUACGGAGGCAUGUGGAAACAAAAGUUAGAGCUAAAAUCCGUAAGAGGAAGGUGACAACGAAAAUCAACCGUCAUGACAAAAUCAAUGGAAAGAGGAAGACCGCCAGAAAACAGAAAAUGUUUCAACGUGCGCAAGAGUUGCGGCGGCGGGCAGAGGACUACCACAAAUGCAAAAUCCCCCCUUCUGCAAGAAAGCCUCUUUGCAACUGGGUCAGAAUGGCGGCAGCGGAGCAUUGUCAUUCUUCAGGAUUGCCCUACUGGCUCUACCUCACAGCUGAAACUUUAAAAAACAGGAUGGGCCGCCAGCCACCUCCUCCAACUCAACAACAUUCUAUAACUGAUAACUCCCUGAGCCUCAAGACACCUCCCGAGUGUCUGCUCACUCCCCUUCCACCCUCAGUGGAUGAUAAUAUCAAGGAGUGUCCUCUUGCUCCUCUUCCACCCUCUCCUCUUCCACCCUCAGUGGAUGAUAAUCUGAAGGAAUGUCUCUUUGUCCCGCUUCCACCCUCUCCUCUUCCACCCUCAGUGGAUGAUAAUCUGAAGGAAUGUCUCUUUGUCCCGCUUCCACCCUCUCCUCUUCCACCCUCAGUGGAUGAUAAUCUCAAGACUCCUCCCUUAGCUACUCAGGAGGCCGAGGUGGAAAAACCACCCAAACCCAAGAGGUGGAGGGUGGAUGAGGUGGAACAAUCGCCCAAGCCCAAGAGGCAGAGGGAGGCCGAGGCACAACAAUUACCCAAACCCAAGAGGCGGAGGUUGAGUAAGCUGAGAACACGCCAUUGCACUCAAGCCUGGGCAAUAAGAAUAAAUCCGUAGGUCGAAAAAAAGAAAAAAAUCAAAAAACAAAACAAAACCCACGCUCCAAAAACAAACUAACGAAGAAUAAAUAAAUAAUAUAAAAAUAAAAUAAA